UAUUCCCGGCCCUUUGGGAGGCCGAGACAGGCGGAUGACAUGAGGUCAGGAGUUUAAGACCAGCCUGGCCAACAUGGCAAAAAUCCUGUCUCUACUAAAAGUACAAAAAUUAGCCAGGCGUGGUGGCAGGCACCUAUAAUCCCAGCCACUCAGGAGGCUGAGGCAGGAGAAUUGCUUGAACUCAGGAGGCGGAAGUUGCAGUGAGCUGAGAUCGCACCACUGCACUCCAGCCUGGGCAACAGAGUGAGACUCCAUCUAAAAAAAAAAAAAGAAGAAGAGGUUAGACUUAACUGUUUCCAAGAUUUCAUCCAGUUGUGAAAUCCUGUUAUCUGAACUGCCAGGCCUACAAGUUCAAUUCAAAAGAUGGAAUGUAGCUUCCUGCAGUCUUUAAAUGAACAAAACAAACAGCACAAGCUACACUGCGAAGAUGAGUCUGCACUACAUAUCUUUCUUUUUGCCCCCAGGAACCUGGCUUACCAGUAUAUCACCCCAGCGUUGACACACUGGGAACGGGUCACGCAUGUGGAUGAUCAAAGGUCAGCUCCUGGUCAAUAUGAGAAGACUGGUUUCAGAAAAGUUGAGUGCUGAAGACUACAAAGCUGUUUGUGUUGGAAAUCAAUAGCUCUUCUAGCCUUUGCAUUGUUUAAAUAUAAUAGUGUCAUUGGACUAAGAUGUUCCUGAUGCCAACCUCUUCAGAGUUAAACAGUGGGCAGAACUUCCUAACCCAGUGGAUGACCAAUCCUUCUCGGGCUGGGGUCAUAUUAAAUCGUGGAUUUCCUAUUUUGGAAGCAGACAAAGAGAAGCGAGCAGCUGUGGACAUUUCUACCAGCUUUCCUAUUAAAGGCACACAUUUUUCUGAUAGCUUCAGCUUUAUAAAUGAAGAAGAUUCACUUCUUGAAGAACAGAAGUUGGAGUCAAACAACCCUUACAAACCACAGUCAGAUAAAUCUGAAACCCAUACAGCCUUUCCUUGCAUUAAAAAGGGACCACAGGUAGCGGCAUGUCACAGUGCUCCUGGACACCAGGAAGAAAACAAAAAUGACUUCAUCCCAGAUCUUGCGAGUGAAUUCAAAGAAGGGGCUUAUAAAGACCCACUUUUUAAAAAACUUGAACAGCUGAAAGAAGUACAACAGAAGAAGCAGGAACAAUUGAAGAGGCAACAGUUGGAGCAACUACAGAGACUCAUGGAAGAACAAGAGAAGCUGCUCACCAUGGUGUCUGGGCAGUGCACACUUCCAGGUUUGAGUUUACUGCCUGAUGAUCAGAGCCAGAAGCACAGGUCUCCAGGAAAUACCACCACUGGAGAGAGAGCCACAUGCUGCUUCCCAUCAUAUGUCUACCCGGACCCAACCCAGGAAGAAACAUACCCGUCCAACAUUUUAUCCCAUGAGCAAAGCAACUUCUGUAGAACUGCUCAUGGAGAUUUUGUCUUAACUUCAAAACGUGCGUCUCCUAAUUUAUUUUCUGAGGCACAGUAUCAAGAAGCACCUGUGGAAAAAAAUAAUUUAAAAGAAGAAAACCGUAACCAUCCUACAGGAGAAAGUAUCUUAUGUUGGGAGAAAGUGACAGAACAGAUUCAGGAAGCAAAUGAUAAGAACUUACAAAAACAUGAUGAUUCCUCAGAAGUGGCUAAUAUUGAAGAAAGGCCCAUUAAAGCUGCUAUUGGAGAAAGGAAACAGACCUUUGAAGAUUACUUAGAAGAACAAAUUCAGUUGGAAGAGCAAGAACUGAAGCAAAAACAGCUGAAGGAAGCAGAAGGACCAUUGCCAAUCAAAGCAAAACCAAAACAACCAUUUUUAAAACGAGGAGAAGGUUUAGCUAGAUUUACUAAUGCCAAAUCUAAGUUUCAAAAAGGCAAAGAAAGUAAACUAGUGACUAACCAGAGCACUUCCGAGGACCAGCCGCUGUUUAAAAUGGAUAGACAGCAACUCCAGCGGAAAACCGCUCUUAAAAAUAAAGAGCUGUGUGCAGACAACCCUAUCCUUAAAAAGGACAGUAAAGCUAGAACCAAGAGUGGUUCUGUCACCCUCAGUCAGAAGCCGAAAAUGCUGAAGUGUAGUAACAGGAAAAGUCUUUCUCCGUCAGGAUUGAAAAUACAGACGGGGAAGAAAUGUGAUGGGCAGUUUAGAGACCAGAUCAAAUUUGAAAACAAAGUCACAUCUAAUAAUAAAGAAAAUGUAACUGAGUGUCCAAAACCUUGCGAUACUGGCUGCACAGGGUGGAAUAAGACACAAGGUAAAGACAGACUUCCUCUUUCAACAGGGCCGGCCAGCCGGCUGGCUGCUAAGAGCCCCAUAAGGGAGACCAUGAAAGAGUCUGAAUCUUCUCUUGACGUUUCUCUUCAGAAAAAGUUAGAGACUUGGGAACGAGAAAAGGAAAAGGAAAAUUUGGAAUUAGAUGAAUUUUUGUUUUUAGAACAAGCUGCUGAUGAAAUAUCAUUUUCUAGUAAUUCCUCAUUUGUACUGAAAAUCUUAGAAAGGGAUCAACAGAUCUGCAAAGGUCACCGGAUGUCUUCCACCCCUGUCAAAGCUGUGCCACAGAAGACAAAUCCGGCAGAUCCCAUUAGUCAUUGUAACCGCAGUGAGGAUUUGGACCACACUGCACGUGAGAAGGAGAGUGAGUGUGAAGUCGCACCCAAACAACUUCAUUCAUUGUCCUCAGCUGAUGAAUUGAGGGAACAGCCUUGUAAAAUCAGGAAAGCCGUCCAAAAGAGCACUUCUGAAAAUCAGACUGAAUGGAAUGCACGUGACGAUGAAGGUGUUCCAAAUAGUGACAGUAGCACUGACUCUGAGGAACAGCUUGAUGUUACCAUAAAACCAUCGACUGAGGAUAGAGAGAGGGGCAUCAGCAGCAGAGAGGAUAGCCCACAAGUCUGUGAUGAUAAGGGGCCUUUUAAGGACACCAGGACCCAAGAAGAUAAAAGGAGAGAUGUUGAUCUGGAUUUGUCUGAUAAAGAUUACAGUAGCGAUGAGUCUAUCAUGGAAAGCAUAAAACAUAAAGUGUCUGAGCCCUCGAGAUCCUCAUCCCUAAGUCUGAGUAAAAUGGACUUUGAUGAUGAAAGAACUUGGACUGACCUUGAAGAGAAUUUGUGUAACCAUGAUGUUGUUCUUGGGAAUGAAUCCACUUAUGGGACGCCGCAGACAUGCUACCCUAAUAAUGAAAUAGGUAUCCUGGACAAAACAAUAAAAAGGAAGAUUGCACCAGUCAAGAGGGGAGAAGACUUGAGCAAGUCCAGGAGGAGCAGAAGUCCUCCUACAUCGGAGCUGAUGAUGAAAUUCUUUCCUUCUUUGAAACCAAAACCAAAGUCAGAUUCACACUUGGGAAAUGAACUCAAGUUAAACAUAAGUCAAGACCAACCACCUGGUGACAAUGCUCGAUCCCAGGUUUUGAGAGAGAAAAUUAUUGAAUUGGAAACAGAAAUAGAAAAGUUUAAAGCUGAGAACGCAUCUUUAGCUAAACUUCGCAUUGAACGAGAAAGUGCCUUGGAAAAACUCAGGAAAGAAAUUGCAGACUUCGAACAACAGAAAGCAAAAGAAUUAGCUCGAAUAGAAGAGUUUAAAAAGGAGGAGAUGAGGAAGCUACAAAAGGAACGUAAAGUUUUUGAAAAGUAUACUACAGCUGCAAGAACUUUUCCAGAUAAAAAGGAACGUGAAGAAAUACAGACUUUAAAACAGCAAAUAGCAGAUUUACGGGAAGAUUUGAAAAGAAAGGAAACCAAAUGGUCAAGUACACACAGCCGUCUCAGAAGCCAGAUACAAAUGUUAGUCAGAGAGAACACAGACCUCCGGGAAGAAAUAAAAGUGAUGGAAAGAUUCCGACUGGAUGCCUGGAAGAGAGCAGAAGCCAUAGAGAGCAGCCUCGAGGUGGAGAAGAAGGACAAGCUUGCGAACACAUCUGUUCGAUUUCAAAACAGUCAGAUUUCUUCAGGAACCCAGGUAGAAAAAUACAAGAAAAAUUAUCUUCCAAUGCAAGGCAAUCCACCUCGAAGAUCCAAGUCUGCACCUCCUCGUGAUUUAGGCAAUUUGGAUAAGGGACAAGCUGCCUCUCCCAGGGAGCCACUUGAACCACUGAACUUCCCAGAUCCUGAAUAUAAAGAGGAGGAGGAAGACCAAGACAUACAGGGAGAAAUCAGUCAUCCUGAUGGAAAGGUGGAAAAGGUUUAUAAGAAUGGGUGCCGUGUUAUACUGUUUCCCAAUGGAACUCGAAAGGAAGUGAGUGCAGAUGGGAAGACCAUCACUGUCACUUUCUUUAAUGGUGACGUGAAGCAGGUCAUGCCAGACCAAAGAGUGAUCUACUACUAUGCAGCUGCCCAGACCACUCACACGACAUACCCGGAGGGACUGGAAGUCUUACAUUUCUCAAGUGGACAAAUAGAAAAACAUUACCCAGAUGGAAGAAAAGAAAUCACGUUUCCUGACCAGACUGUUAAAAACUUAUUUCCUGAUGGACAAGAAGAAAGCAUUUUCCCAGAUGGUACAAUUGUCAGAGUACAACGUGAUGGCAACAAACUCAUAGAGUUUAAUAAUGGCCAAAGAGAACUACAUACUGCCCAGUUCAAGAGACGGGAAUACCCAGAUGGCACUGUUAAAACCGUAUAUGCAAACGGUCAUCAAGAAACGAAGUACAGAUCCGGUCGGAUAAGAGUUAAGGACAAGGAGGGUAAUGUGCUAAUGGACACGGAGCUGUGACGAUCCUCAUGUGAUCAUGAAGUAACAGUAACUGACUUUUUAUGUUAAAAAAUGUACAUUUACUGUGGAUUCUGUUUAAUUUAUUGUGUAUGUGUGGGGAAAAGAUUAGAUUCUAAAAUAAAAGUUUACCCUGUGGCAUCUUCAUUUUUAUAUUCUUUGAAAUGCAAUGAUAGCUCUCAUUUAUAAUUCACUACCCUGUCUUUCAAUAGACUAAGGAAAGCAUUUUGACUGUUUAGAAAUUGUGUACAGGUUUUUACAGUAAGUGGGUGUGUUUAUUGGUUAGAAAUGGCUAUAAAAAAAAACCAAGAAGUACAGGAAGUACAUCACCUAGAUGUCCCACAGACACAUCAGCCGUAGAGCACUGGACUUGUACAGAAGGUGUACUCAAGGAGUAAACACGUGUCUCUGUAGCCAAAAUAUUACUAUGUUCAGUUAGUACCAAAAUUAGACCAUUUGAUCUUCUACAGAGGAUCAUUAAUUAUUAUAACAGAAUGGGAAGUUACAACAGUGGAUGAAUAUAAAUAGGUCACACACAACAGGUAGUAAUCAUGGUGAAGAGAAAGCAGUUAUAACAAGGCUGACUUUGUAAUGUAAUGUCUCAAAAUGGGAUACUUGAGAGUGGAGGGGGGCAUGAACGAUGACUAGCCAGUGUUAACCCAUGGACCACAGCUACCCUGAUGUUACCACAGUGAGAUUACUGUAGCCUCAUGGAAGCAAGAUGUCCCUGAAGGAUGGGCAAGUCACUUACUUACUUACUUGUAAAUUUAUAUAAUAAAUAAUUACAGAUUGGUCUAGAUAGACCUUACCUGUCACAUAUACUAUGAAUCAGGUUUUGUUAAUGAAAUCUAUCAAUUCCAGGUGACUUAACUGAAUAUGAAAAAUAAAACUUUUUGAAGAA